GUCUCUCCCUUCAGCCCGAGCUCCGGGUCUCGUCUUCACUGCUCUGUGUCCUCUUCUUCUAGAGGCCCAGCCUCUAUGGCCCUCUGACCUGCAGGUAUUGGCGAUCCAUAGCUAAGACGCCAGGUCCCCCGGAAACCUAGAAAUGGAACCAUUGAAAUUUAGGGAUGUGGCCAUAGAAUUCUCUCUGGAGGAGUGGCAAUGCCUGGACACUAUACAGCAGAAUUUAUAUAGGAAUGUGAUGUUAGAGAACUACAGAAACCUGGUCUUCUUGGGUAUUGUUGUCUCUAAGCCAGACCUGAUCACCUGUCUGGAACAAGAAAAAGAGCCUUGGACUAGAAAGAGACAUAGGAUGGUGGCCGAACCCCCAGUUAUUUGUUCUCAUUUUGCCCAAGACUUUUCACCAGAGCAGAACAUAAAAGAUUCUUUCCAAAAAGUGACACCAAGAAGAUAUGGAAAAUGUGAACAUGAGAAUUUACAGUUAAGUAAAAGUGUGGAUGAGUGCAAAGUGCAAAAAGGAGGUUAUAAUGGACUUAACCAAUGUUUGCCAACUACCCAGAGCAAAAUAUUUCAAUGUGAUAAAUAUAUGAAAAUCUUUCAUAAAUUUUCAAAUUUAAAUGGACAUAAGGUAAGACACACCAGAAAAAAACCUUUUAAAUAUAAAGAAUUUGGCAAAUCAUUUUGCAUAUUUUCAAACCUAACUCAACAUAAAAUAAUUUGUACUAGAGUAAAUUUCUACAAAUGUGAAGACUGUGGAAAAGCCUUUAAUGGAUCCUCAAUCUUUACUAAACAUAAAAGAAUUCAUAUUGGAGAGAAAUCGUACAUAUGUGAAGAAUGUGGCAAAGCCUGUAACCAGUUCACAAACCUUACUACACAUAAGAUAAUUUAUACUAGAGACAAACUCUACAAACGUGAAGAAUGUAGCAAAGCCUUUAACCUGUCGUCACACAUUACAACACAUACAAUAAUUCAUACUGGAGAGAAUCCCUACAAACGUGAAGAAUGUGACAAAGCCUUUAAUCAGUCCUUAACCCUUACUACACAUAAGAUAAUUCAUACCAGAGAGAAACUCAAUGAAUAUAAGGAAUGUGGCAAAGCUUUCAACCAGUCCUCACACCUUACCAGACAUAAGAUAAUUCAUACUGGAGAGAAACCCUACAAAUGUGAAGAAUGUGGCAAAGCCUUUAACCAGUCCUCACACCUUACCAGACAUAAGAUAAUUCAUACUGGAGAGAAGCCCUACAGAUGUGAAGAAUGUGGCAAAGCCUUUAGGCAGUCCUCACACCUUACUACACAUAAGAUAAUUCAUACUGGAGAGAAACCCUACAAAUGUGAAGAAUGUGGCAAAGCUUUUAACAAGUCCUCACACCUUACUAGACAUAAGAGCAUUCAUACUGGAGAAAAACCCUACCAGUGUGAAAAAUGUGGCAAAGCUUCUAACCAAUCCUCAAACCUUACUGAACAUAAGAAUAUUCAUACUGAAGAGAAACCAUACAAAUGUGAAGAAUGUGGGAAAGCCUUUAACCAGUUCUCAAACCUUACUACACAUAAAAGAAUUCAUACUGGAGAGAAACCCUACAAAUGUGAAGAAUGUGGCAAAGCUUUUAACCAGUCCUCAAUCCUUACUACACAUAAGAGAAUUCAUACUGGAGAGAAAUCCUACAAAUGUGAAGAAUGUGGCAAAGCUUUCUAUCGAUCCUCAAAACUUACUGAACAUAAGAAAAUUCAUACUGGAGAGAAACCCUACACAUGUGAAGAAUGUGGCAAAGCCUUUAACCAUUCCUCACAUCUUGCUACACAUAAGGUAAUUCAUACUGGAGAGAAACCCUACCAAUGUGAAGAAUGUGGUAAAGCCUUUAACCAGUCCUCACACCUUACUAGACAUAAGAGAAUUCAUACUGGAGAGAAACCCUACCAAUGUGAAAAAUGUGGCAAAGCUUUUAACCAGUCCUCAAACCUUACUGGACAUAAGAAAAUUCAUACUGGUGAGAAACUCUACAAACCUAAAAGAUGUAACAGUGAUUUUGAAAACACUUCAAAGUUUUCUAAACAUAAAAGAAAUUAUGCUGGUGAGAAAUCUUAGAAAUGUGAAGAAUGUAACAAAACCUUUAAAAGUUGUCACACUUGAUUGUGCAUAAGAUAAUUCAUACUAAAAAAAAACCUACAAGUGUGAAGAAUGUGGCAAAACUUUUAACCAAUGCUCACACCUUAUUGCACAGGAAAGCAUUUGUACUAGAAAAAAAUUUCAAAUAUACAGAAUGUGAAAAAGCCAUUAAUAUCUGUUCACAUCUUACUCAACAUCAGAGAUUUCAUACUUAAUAAAAGCAUUAUACAUGCAAUUACUGUCAAAAAUCUUUCAGAAAAUAUAAGCCUCUAAAGUGAAGAGUAUUCAUUUUGAAGACACACAUUAUGAACAUAAGGAGGGUUGUGGUACCUUUACUUGUAUCACAGAUCUCAUUGUACACAUUUUGUGCUAGAGGAAAACCAUGGAGCAGUUGCUUAAACUUUGUGCAACAUAAGGAAAUUUAUAUUGGAGAAAAACCCUGCAAAUGUAAUAAAUUUGGGAAAACAUUUUUUCAAAAACGACAGCUUAGAAAACACUAGAGGGUUCAUACUAAAAUCUAUUUUUGCAGAUGCAGUAAAUAUGAAAAAAUAUUUAAUCCAAAAUUCUAUGUAAAUAUCAGAUAAUUCACAGUAGAAAUAGUUAAGGCACUGACACUUCAGGCAUUACACUAAAUCAGAUUGCUGAGUAUAGAAAAGAAUCUAAAACUAAAGUUGGUAAAUGAAUUAUUUGUAUAUAACAUUAUAAGAAGUAGAAAAUUUUUGCAGAGUUGUAACUACAUUCAAACUAUCCUUUGAAAAAAAUUAGGUUUUAUGAAAAGUGAAUAAUGUCAUUUAACUCAAGUUAUGCUCUUCAUUCCUAUUGUAUUCACAUGUGAAAGCAUGUGACUUAAUUGUUGCUGCAUCAAAGAUGAGAGAUUCUUUGUUAUUAGGUGUGCAUUAUUUACGACCUUUUUUAGUGAAAGAGUUAAGGACAUUAAAAUGUAAGAUGCAAGAUGAAAAUGUAAGUGGAGAGGCUCUUUCUGGUUAAUUUAUAAUAUUGACUGAUGCAUGAGGUAGGAGUUCAGAUAAAUAUCCUGUGUUAUAUUGAGAAAAAAAAUUUUCUGGUAUAUCAUUUUACUAAUUGUACUUUUUUUUUUUUUGAGACAGAGUUUUGCUCUUGUUGCCCAGGCUGGAGUGCAAUGGUGUGAUCUUGGCUCACCAAAACCUCCACCUCCCAGGUUCAAGGGAUUCUCCUGCCUCAGCCUCCCGAGUAGCUGGGAUUACAGGCAUGUGCCACCAUGCCCGGCUAAUUUUGUAUUUUUAAUAGAGAUGGGGUUUCUCUAUGUUGGUCAGGCUGGUCUCAAACUCCCGACCUCGGGUGAUCCACCCACCUCGGCCUCCCAAAGUGCUGGGAUUACAGGCGCGAGUCACCAUGCCUGGCCAAUUGUACUUUUAUGUAAUAAAAUGUAGUACAUUUUAAAAUUUUUAGAUAAUGUGUGAACUUAUUAAUCAGGCUUUUUAAAAAACAUGUUAAGACCAUCGUGCAUUCAAUGAAGCAUUAUUAUGCCAUUAAAUUUAACUUAUCCCAUCUUACUCAAGGGUAUAGGUAAAUGAUGGUAACUAUACACUAUUUAAUAAGAUAAUGGACUAACAUUUCUAGUAAUCUGUUUUGCCAGUGGCUUUAAAUUGCAAAUAAGUCAGAGAAUAUUAUUCCUGUAGGUUGAAUUAUUACUCAUUUUUUCUUAUUUAAACUUAUUUUUCUUAAUUUUUGUGGGUACAUAGUAUGUGUAAAUAUGGCAUAUAUGGCAUAUUUUGAUACAGGUAUAUAAUAUGUAAUAAUUACAUAUGGGUAAAUGAAAUAUUCAUUACCUGCAGCAUUUAUUGUUUGUAUUUGUUUGUAUUAUAAACUAAUUCUGCACUUUUCGGUUUUUUUUUGAGACGAGUCUCACUAUGUCACCCAGGCUGUGCACGCCUGGGUGCAUUGGCGUGGUCUCAGCUCACUGCAACCUCCGCCUACUGGGUUCAAGUGAUUCUUCCGCCUCAGCCUCCUGAGUAGUUGGGACUACAGGCGCAUGCCACCACACUCAGCUAAUUUUUGUAUUUUUAGUAGAAACAGUUUCACUACGUUGGCCAGGUUUGUCUUGAACUCCUGACCCCAUGAUUAGCCCCCUCGGCCUCCCAAAGUGCUGGGAUUACAGGUGGGAGCCACCACACCCAGCCACUUUUAGUUGUUUUCAAAUGUACAUUAAAUUGUUGUUGGCUACAGGGUCUCUUUUAUGGUCAUAAGAAAACAAUAUAAACAAAAUGCAUACAUUUCUGAGACCUGAAUUAACAUUAAAAAAUUGUUAUAUAUUUUUCUUCAAACAUGUUGCCUCUCUGCCUGCAAGCACAUACAGACUAUUAGUUUUGAUUUACACAGAGUUAAAUAUAUACAUAUAUUACUUUAAAGAUAAAGCUUGGGUUUAAAAAAAUUAUGGAGUAAAUAAAUGCCUUCUUUGCGAGUAUGAGUUUCUACCUAGUUUCAGAAGAGCAAUAUUGAAACAAAUCAAAUUAUUUUAAUUAGAUGAUGACUGCAAAACUAAAAAAACUUAAAAAUGCUGAAAACAAAUCCAUACUCUCUGCUUUGUAUUGAAUUGAUUACUGUAAAAUUGUAUGGCUUAUAAUUCAGAAUCUCCCUAUGCAAAUUUUUGUUUUUACUUGCCUGAUUCUUAGGCUAGACCCAUAAUUUUCUUGUGUCUUACAUUUUUUUCUCUUAUUUUAUAUAAGAUGCUAUGUGAGCUGGUCAGAGAUUAUAAAAAUAAUUUUUAUAAAAUUAGUGCAAAAAAUUUAGAUUUAAUUUCAAAAUUAGUGUAUUGUUAUAUUUUAUGUUGUUAGAAUAUUUUAUUUUGUUCUUUUAAUUGGAGAACGCUGUAUAAGCCUACUUUUUUUAGUUUUUGUUCCUUUCAGUUUUUAUAAUGAAAAUAAGUAAAUAUUGAUUGAGCCCAUUUAUUUAGGUGAGUACUAGGGGGGCUUCCUAAAUCAUGAGGAUGUUUUUAUAUAUAAAUAUAGCAAACAAACAUGACAGUGCUUUCUGUGUCACAGAUGCUUUAUAAUAAGCCAUAAAUAUUCCUGUUGGAGUUAGUUUGUAACUUCAAGACAGAGAUGGAACAUAUCAAUUGUGAGAAAUAACAUUGAUUUUUUAUGUGGAGAGGACAUUUAUUUUCAGGCUGCAAAGCUCAGUUUUGCUGAAUUAAAAAAUUGUGCUUCUUUUAUUUCCUAAUUGUCUUAGUUUUGUUUGUCUUAUUAUGUGUAUUUCAGCUGUGUAUGCAUCACAGCCCUCCUUUUUGCUGUGCUGUGGCUACAGUUUUCUCACUGUUCUCUUCACACCAUGUCAUUUCACAUGGUAUAUUGUAGGUUUUGAUGAGAAAUCGGUAUUUUUAAUGCACUGCAAGAUUGGUUUUAACUGGAGAUUUUGCAUAUCAAUAUAAUUUUCUGAUCAGUUAAAUUAAAACAAAAAGCAUACAGUGUCCACAGAUGAAAGGAUUAAAUCAUUUAGCGUUGUUUUUCUCUGUUUGUUAAAGAAUAAUCUUAUUAAAUUCUUACACAAAGUGUGGCAAAUAUAAAAUUUGCUUGAAAAUAUAUCUUAGAAAUUAAACUUUUAAUUUAAUUUUCUACAGUAUACUUAUGCCACAAUGUACGUUUCCAUGCAAAAUCUUCUAUUUGUAAGUGUGAACAUUAAACAUUGCAAAAUAGUAAAAUGACCUCUGUGAUUUUGAAACCUGGAGUAAUAUUUCUUUUCCAUAUUCAUAUUACAAUUUGAAGAAAUUUUCUCAGUUUUAUAUGUUUUUUUAGUGGGUGAAGUUCAGUCUACAGUUUUUACAUUUAGUCACCUAACUCUAGCCAACUUCUUGGUCAUAUUCUCUGGAAAACAUUCGAAGAUCAUGGCAGCUUUUAGAUAAAAACAUUUUCUAUUAUUUUGCGUGCAAACUUGUUUACUGUGUUCACAGAGUGGCCAGUCAUGAGACCAUAAGAAACAGCUGCCCUUUUAGUGUCUUUCAUACCGUCUGUAAUAUAUAAAUUGUGCAUUUAUUCUGUGAAGCAUGACAUUUUGAAGUAUAUACACAUUGUCAAAUGCUUCAUUCUAGGUAAUUAAUGCUUUACCUAACAUAGUUAACAUUUUUGUGGUAAGAGCACAUGACAAUGUUUUAGCAUUUUUCAGAAAUACAAAUACAUUGUUAUGAACUAUAGGCACCAUGCAGUACAAAAGCUUUUUUGAACUUAUUUCUCCUAUUCAACUGUAAUUAUGUAUUUGACUGACAUCUUUCUAAACCCCUCUUUUUUCCAAAUAUGUUGGCAUCUGGUGGUCACCAUUUUAUUCUCCACUUCAGUUAGAUUAAUUUUUCUAGAAUCAUGUAAGUGAAAUAAUUUGGUUAAUCUAUGUAAUUGAAAAUAAUAAAUUUUUUUAUUUUAAAGAUGAA